GCAGUCACCGCCACCCACCAGCUCCGGCACCAACAGCAGCGCCGCUGCCACCGCCCACCUUCUGCCGCCGCCACCACAGCCACCUUCUCCUCCUCCGCUGUCCUCUCCCGUCCUCGCCUCUGUCGACUAUCAGGUGAACUUUGAACCAGGAUGGCUGAGCCCCGCCAGGAGUUCGAAGUGAUGGAAGAUCACGCUGGGACGUACGGGUUGGGGGACAGGAAAGAUCAGGGGGGCUACACCAUGCACCAAGACCAAGAGGGUGACACGGACGCUGGCCUGAAAGAAUCUCCCCUGCAGACCCCCACUGAGGACGGAUCUGAGGAACCGGGCUCUGAAACCUCUGAUGCUAAGAGCACUCCAACAGCGGAAGAUGUGACAGCACCCUUAGUGGAUGAGGGAGCUCCCGGCAAGCAGGCUGCCGCGCAGCCCCACACGGAGAUCCCAGAAGGAACCACAGCUGAAGAAGCAGGCAUUGGAGACACCCCCAGCCUGGAAGACGAAGCUGCUGGUCACGUGACCCAAGAGGAGUUGAGAGUUCCGGGCCGGCAGAGGAAGGCGCCUGAAAGGCCCCUGGCCAAUGAGAUUAGCGCCCACGUCCAGCCUGGACCCUGCGGAGAGGCCUCUGGGGUCUCUGGGCCGUGCCUCGGGGAGAAAGAGCCAGAAGCUCCCGUCCCGCUGACCGCGAGCCUUCCUCAGCACCGUCCCGUUUGCCCAGCGCCUCCUCCAACAGGAGGCCCUCAGGAGCCCUCCCUGGAGUGGGGACAAAAAGGCGGGGACUGGGCCGAGAAGGGUCCGGCCUUUCCGAAGCCCGCCACCACUGCGUAUCUCCACACAGAGCCUGAAAGUGGUAAGGUGGUCCAGGAAGGCUUCCUCCGAGAGCCAGGCCCCCCAGGUCUGAGCCACCAGCUCAUGUCCGGCAUGCCUGGGGCUCCCCUCCUGCCUGAGGGCCCCAGAGAGGCCACACGCCAACCUUCGGGGACAGGACCUGAGGACACAGAGGGCGGCCGCCACGCCCCUGAGCUGCUCAAGCACCAGCUUCUAGGAGACCUGCACCAGGAGGGGCCGCCGCUGAAGGGGGCAGGGGGCAAAGAGAGGCCGGGGAGCAAGGAGGAGGUGGAUGAAGACCGCGACGUCGAUGAGUCCUCCCCCCAAGACUCCCCUCCCUCCAAGGCCUCCCCAGCCCAAGAUGGGCGGCCUCCCCAGACAGCCGCCAGAGAAGCCACCAGCAUCCCAGGCUUCCCAGCGGAGGGUGCCAUCCCCCUCCCUGUGGAUUUCCUCUCCAAAGUUUCCACAGAGAUCCCAGCCUCAGAGCCCGACGGGCCCAGUGUAGGGCGGGCCAAAGGGCAGGAUGCCCCCCUGGAGUUCACGUUUCACGUGGAAAUCACACCCAACGUGCAGAAGGAGCAGGCGCACUCGGAGGAGCAUUUGGGAAGGGCUGCAUUUCCAGGGGCCCCUGGAGAGGGGCCAGAGGCCCGGGGCCCCUCUUUGGGAGAGGACACAAAAGAGGCUGACCUUCCAGAGCCCUCUGAAAAGCAGCCUGCUGCUGCUCCGCGGGGGAAGCCCGUCAGCCGGGUCCCUCAACUCAAAGCUCGCAUGGUCAGUAAAAGCAAAGACGGGACUGGAAGCGAUGACAAAAAAGCCAAGACAUCCACACGUUCCUCUGCUAAAACCUUGAAAAAUAGGCCUUGCCUUAGCCCCAAACACCCCACUCCUGGUAGCUCAGACCCUCUGAUCCAACCCUCCAGCCCUGCUGUGUGCCCAGAGCCACCUUCCUCUCCUAAAUACGUCUCUUCUGUCACUUCCCGAACUGGCAGUUCUGGAGCAAAGGAGAUGAAACUCAAGGGGGCUGAUGGUAAAACGAAGAUCGCCACACCGCGGGGAGCAGCCCCUCCAGGCCAGAAGGGCCAGGCCAACGCCACCAGGAUUCCAGCAAAAACCCCGCCCGCUCCAAAGACACCACCCAGCUCUGGUGAACCUCCAAAAUCAGGGGAUCGCAGCGGCUACAGCAGCCCCGGCUCCCCAGGCACUCCCGGCAGCCGCUCCCGCACCCCGUCCCUUCCAACCCCACCCACCCGGGAGCCCAAGAAGGUGGCAGUGGUCCGUACUCCACCCAAGUCGCCGUCUUCCGCCAAGAGCCGCCUGCAGACAGCCCCCGUGCCCAUGCCAGACCUGAAGAAUGUCAAGUCCAAGAUCGGCUCCACUGAGAACCUGAAGCACCAGCCGGGAGGCGGGAAGGUGCAGAUAAUUAAUAAGAAGCUGGAUCUUAGCAACGUCCAGUCCAAGUGUGGCUCAAAGGAUAAUAUCAAACACGUCCCGGGAGGCGGCAGUGUGCAAAUAGUCUACAAACCAGUUGACCUGAGCAAGGUGACCUCCAAGUGUGGCUCAUUAGGCAACAUCCAUCAUAAACCAGGAGGUGGCCAGGUGGAAGUAAAAUCUGAGAAGCUUGACUUCAAGGACAGAGUCCAGUCGAAGAUUGGGUCCCUGGACAAUAUCACCCACGUCCCUGGCGGAGGAAAUAAAAAGAUUGAAACCCACAAGCUGACCUUCCGCGAGAACGCCAAAGCCAAGACAGACCACGGGGCGGAGAUCGUGUACAAGUCGCCAGUGGUGUCUGGGGACACGUCUCCACGGCAUCUCAGCAAUGUCUCCUCCACCGGCAGCAUCGACAUGGUAGACUCGCCCCAGCUCGCCACGCUAGCUGACGAGGUGUCUGCCUCCCUGGCCAAGCAGGGUUUGUGAUCAGGCCCCUGGGGCGGUCAAUAAUUGUGGAGAGGAGAGAAUGAGAGAGUGUGGAAAAAAAAAGAAUAAUGACCCGGCCCCCGCCCUCUGCCCCCAGCUGCUCCUCGCAGUUCGGUUAAUUGGUUAAUCACUUAACCUGCUUUUGUCACUCGGCUUUGGCUCGGGACUUCAAAAUCAGUGAUGGGAGUAAGAGCAAAUUUCAUCUUUCCAAAUUGAUGGGUGGGCUAGUAAUAAAAUAUUUAAAAAAAAACAUUCAAAAACAUGGCCACAUCCAACAUUUCCUCAGGCAAUUCCUUUUGAUUCUUUUUUCUUCCCCCUCCAUGUAGAAGAGGGAGAAGGAGAGGCUCUGAAAGCUGCUUCUGGGGGAUUUCAAGGGACUGGGGGUGCCAACCACCUCUGGCCCUGUUGUGGGGGUGUCACAGAGGCAGUGGCAGCAACAAAGGAUUUGAAACUUGGUGUGUUCGUGGAGCCACAGGCAGACGAUGUCAACCUUGUGUGAGUGUGACGGGGGUUGGGGUGGGGCGGGAGGCCACGGGGGAGGCCGAGGCAGGGGCUGGGCAGAGGGGAGAGGAAGCACAAGAAGUGGGAGUGGGAGAGGAAGCCACGUGCUGGAGAGUAGACAUCCCCCUCCUUGCCGCUGGGAGAGCCAAGGCCUAUGCCACCUGCAGCGUCUGAGCGGCCGCCUGUCCUUGGUGGCCGGGGGUGGGGGCCUGCUGUGGGUCAGUGUGCCACCCUCUGCAGGGCAGCCUGUGGGAGAAGGGACAGCGGGUAAAAAGAGAAGGCAAGCUGGCAGGAGGGUGGCACUUCGUGGAUGACCUCCUUAGAAAAGACUGACCUUGAUGUCUUGAGAGCGCUGGCCUCUUCCUCCCUCCCUGCAGGGUAGGGGGCCUGAGUUGAGGGGCUUCCCUCUGCUCCACAGAAACCCUGUUUUAUUGAGUUCUGAAGGUUGGAACUGCUGCCAUGAUUUUGGCCACUUUGCAGACCUGGGACUUUAGGGCUAACCAGUUCUCUUUGUAAGGACUUGUGCCUCUUGGGAGACGUCCACCCGUUUCCAAGCCUGGGCCACUGGCAUCUCUGGAGUGUGUGGGGGUCUGGGAGGCAGGUCCCGAGCCCCCUGUCCUUCCCACGGCCACUGCAGUCACCCCGUCUGCGCCGCUGUGCUGUUGUCUGCCGUGAGAGCCCAAUCACUGCCUAUACCCCUCAUCACACGUCACAAUGUCCCGAAUUCCCAGCCUCACCACCCCUUCUCAGUAAUGACCCUGGUUGGUUGCAGGAGGUACCUACUCCAUACUGAGGGUGAAAUUAAGGGAAGGCAAAGUCCAGGCACAAGAGUGGGACCCCAGCCUCUCACUCUCAGUUCCACUCAUCCAACUGGGACCCUCACCACGAAUCUCAUGAUCUGAUUCGGUUCCCUGUCUCCUCCUCCCGUCACAGAUGUGAGCCAGGGCACUGCUCAGCUGUGACCCUAGGUGUUUCUGCCUUGUUGACAUGGAGAGAGCCCUUUCCCCUGAGAAGGCCUGGCCCCUUCCUGUGCUGAGCCCACAGCAGCAGGCUGGGUGUCUUGGUUGUCAGUGGUGGCACCAGGAUGGAAGGGCAAGGCACCCAGGGCAGGCCCACAGUCCCGCUGUCCCCCACUUGCACCCUAGCUUGUAGCUGCCAACCUCCCAGACAGCCCAGCCCGCUGCUCAGCUCCACAUGCAUAGUAUCAGCCCUCCACACCCGACAAAGGGGAACACACCCCCUUGGAAAUGGUUCUUUUCCCCCAGUCCCAGCUGGAAGCCAUGCUGUCUGUUCUGCUGGAGCAGCUGAACAUAUACAUAGAUGUUGCCCUGCCCUCCCCAUCUGCACCCUGUUGAGUUGUAGUUGGAUUUGUCUGUUUAUGCUUGGAUUCACCAGAGUGACUAUGAUAGUGAAAAGAAAAAAAAAAAAAAAAAAGGACGCAUGUAUCUUGAAAUGCUUGUAAAGAGGUUUCUAACCCACCCUCACGAGGUGUCUCUCACCCCCACACUGGGACUCGUGUGGCCUGUGUGGUGCCACCCUGCUGGGGCCUCCCAAGUUUUGAAAGGCUUUCCUCAGCACCUGGGACCCAACAGAGACCAGCUUCUAGCAGCUAAGGAGGCCGUUCAGCUGUGACGAAGGCCUGAAGCACAGGAUUAGGACUGAAGCGAUGAUGUCCCCUUCCCUACUUCCCCUUGGGGCUCCCUGUGUCAGGGCACAGACUAGGUCUUGUGGCUGGUCUGGCUUGCGGCGCGAGGAUGGUUCUCUCUGGUCAUAGCCCGAAGUCUCAUGGCAGUCCCAAAGGAGGCUUACAACUCCUGCAUCACAAGAAAAAGGAAGCCACUGCCAGCUGGGGGGAUCUGCAGCUCCCAGAAGCUCCGUGAGCCUCAGCCACCCCUCAGACUGGGUUCCUCUCCAAGCUCGCCCUCUGGAGGGGCAGCGCAGCCUCCCACCAAGGGCCCUGCGACCACAGCAGGGAUUGGGAUGAAUUGCCUGUCCUGGAUCUGCUCUAGAGGCCCAAGCUGCCUGCCUGAGGAAGGAUGACUUGACAAGUCAGGAGACACUGUUCCCAAAGCCUUGACCAGAGCACCUCAGCCCGCUGACCUUGCACAAACUCCAUCUGCUGCCAUGAGAAAAGGGAAGCCGCCUUUGCAAAACAUUGCUGCCUAAAGAAACUCAGCAGCCUCAGGCCCAAUUCUGCCACUUCUGGUUUGGGUACAGUUAAAGGCAACCCUGAGGGACUUGGCAGUAGAAAUCCAGGGCCUCCCCUGGGGCUGGCAGCUUCGUGUGCAGCUAGAGCUUUACCUGAAAGGAAGUCUCUGGGCCCAGAACUCUCCACCAAGAGCCUCCCUGCCGUUCGCUGAGUCCCAGCAAUUCUCCUAAGUUGAAGGGAUCUGAGAAGGAGAAGGAAAUGUGGGGUAGAUUUGGUGGUGGUUAGAGAUAUGCCCCCCUCAUUACUGCCAACAGUUUCGGCUGCAUUUCUUCACGCACCUCGGUUCCUCUUCCUGAAGUUCUUGUGCCCUGCUCUUCAGCACCAUGGGCCUUCUUAUACGGAAGGCUCUGGGAUCUCCCCCUUGUGGGGCAGGCUCUUGGGGCCAGCCUAAGAUCAUGGUUUAGGGUGAUCAGUGCUGGCAGAUAAAUUGAAAAGGCACGCUGGCUUGUGAUCUUAAAUGAGGACAAUCCCCCCAGGGCUGGGCACUCCUCCCCUCCCCUCACUUCUCCCACCUGCAGAGCCAGUGUCCUUGGGUGGGCUAGAUAGGAUAUACUGUAUGCCGGCUCCUUCAAGCUGCUGACUCACUUUAUCAAUAGUUCCAUUUAAAUUGACUUCAGUGGUGAGACUGUAUCCUGUUUGCUAUUGCUUGUUGUGCUAUGGGGGGAGGGGGGAGGAAUGUGUAAGAUAGUUAACAUGGGCAAAGGGAGAUCUUGGGGUGCAGCACUUAAACUGCCUCGUAACCCUUUUCAUGAUUUCAACCACAUUUGCUAGAGGGAGGGAGCAGCCACGGAGUUAGAGGCCCUUGGGGUUUCUCUUUUCCACUGACAGGCUUUCCCAGGCAGCUGGCUAGUUCAUUCCCUCCCCAGCCAGGUGCAGGCGUAGGAAUAUGGACAUCUGGUUGCUUUGGCCUGCUGCCCUCUUUCAGGGGUCCUAAGCCCACAAUCAUGCCUCCCUAAGACCUUGGCAUCCUUCCCUCUAAGCCGUUGGCACCUCUGUGCCACCUCUCACACUGGCUCCAGACACACAGCCUGUGCUUUUGGAGCUGAGAUCACUCGCUUCACCCUCCUCAUCUUUGUUCUCCAAGUAAAGCCACGAGGUCGGGGCGAGGGCAGAGGUGAUCACCUGCGUGUCCCAUCUACAGACCUGCAGCUUCAUAAAACUUCUGAUUUCUCUUCAGCUUUGAAAAGGGUUACCCUGGGCACUGGCCUAGAGCCUCACCUCCUAAUAGACUUAGCCCCAUGAGUUUGCCAUGUUGAGCAGGACUAUUUCUGGCACUUGCAAGUCCCAUGAUUUCUUCGGUAAUUCUGAGGGUGGGGGGAGGGACAUGAAAUCAUCUUAGCUUAGCUUUCUGUCUGUGAAUGUCUAUAUAGUGUAUUGUGUGUUUUAACAAAUGAUUUACACUGACUGUUGCUGUAAAAGUGAAUUUGGAAAUAAAGUUAUUACUCUGAUUAAA